ACAUUUGUCCUGAGUCACCUGUCCAGAGCAGGUGGUGAAUAUUGUGUCCUACUCACGGCAUCUCAACUAUCGGAGCCUGGGAUCUGACUCAAAGGCCGGCCUCCGUCUGAGAACUGAGCGUCCAUUUCUCAAUCCUUGCCGGCUCUGACCCAGGCCUGGGCCACAGGCUGUCCGGGAAUAAGUGGUGCUGCAAUCCCUGCUGGGCAGAUGGAGAGAGGAGCAAGGGAGAUGGCAGCCCCGGGGGACUGUGCAUAGGGAGGUAGGUGGGCACCAGGGACUCAUGAAGUGGCAGCUAAGCCCUGUCCAGUGGCCACCCGUCAGCCAAGGGCCAGAGACCAGGAAAGGAAGAAAGGCAGCUUCACUUCCUCUUUGAGGAUGGAGUCGCACAGCCGCGCUGGAAAGAGCAGAAAAUCUGCAAAAUUUCGGUCCAUCUCCAGGUCCCUGAUGCUCUGUAAUGCUAAGACCAGUGAUGAUGGCUCUAGCCCUGAUGAGAAAUAUCCUGAUCCCUUUGAGAUUUCCUUGGCCCAGGGCAAGGAGGGAAUUUUCCACUCAUCUGUGCAGCUGGCAGACACAUCGGAGGCUGGGCCCAGCAGUGUUCCUGAUCUAGCACUGGCCUCGGAGGCUGCUCAACUCCAAGCAGCUGGGAAUGAUCGAGGCAAGACCUGUAGGAGGAUAUUCUUCAUGAAGGAAUCUUCCACAGCUUCCUCUCGAGAAAAGCCUGGAAAACUAGAAGCACAAAGUAGUAACUUCCUGUUUCCUAAAGCCUGCCACCAAAGGGCACGCAGCAACUCAACCAGUGUUAAUCCCUAUUGCACAAGAGAAAUUGAUUUUCCAAUGACCAAGAAAUCUGCAGCGCCCACGGACAGGCAGCCUUACUCUCUCUGCAGUAACAGGAAGUCCCUCUCUCAACAAUUGGACUGUCCAGCAGGAAAGGCUGCGGGAACUUCGAGACCAACACGGUCCCUGAGCACAGCUCAGCUCGUGCAGCCAUCUGGGGGCCUCCAGGCUUCAGUCAUCUCCAACAUCGUGCUGAUGAAGGGCCAGGCUAAGGGUCUGGGCUUCAGCAUCGUUGGGGGAAAAGACAGCAUUUAUGGCCCCAUUGGGAUUUACGUCAAAACCAUUUUUGCAGGGGGAGCAGCAGCAGCCGAUGGAAGGCUACAGGAAGGUGAUGAAAUUCUGGAGCUCAAUGGUGAAUCAAUGGCUGGACUAACACAUCAGGAUGCUUUGCAGAAGUUCAAGCAAGCCAAAAAGGGGCUCCUCACCCUCACCGUGAGAACCCGCCUGACGGCGCCUCCUUCCCUGUGCAGCCACCUGUCUCCCCCACUGUGCCGCUCCCUGAGCUCCAGCACUUGUAUCACCAAGGACAGCAGCUCCUUCGCCUUGGAAAGCCCCUCGGCUCCCAUCAGCACCGCCAAGCCCAAUUACAGAAUCAUGGUGGAGGUUUCUCUGCAGAAAGAGGCCGGCGUGGGCCUGGGCAUCGGCCUGUGCAGCGUUCCCUACUUCCAAUGCAUCUCUGGCAUUUUCGUCCACACGCUGUCACCAGGAUCCGUGGCGCACCUGGACGGACGUCUCCGGUGUGGGGACGAGAUUGUGGAAAUCAGUGAUUCCCCUGUGCACUGCCUGACGCUCAAUGAAGUCUACACGAUCCUGAGUCACUGUGAUCCCGGUCCAGUCCCCAUCAUUGUUAGCCGACAUCCAGACCCACAGGUCUCUGAACAGCAACUCAAAGAAGCUGUGGCCCAGGCUGUGGAAAACACCAAGUUUGGAAAGGAGAGGCAUCAGUGGAGUCUGGAAGGUGUCAAAAGGCUGGAAAGCAGUUGGCACGGGCGGCCCACCUUGGAGAAGGAACGAGAGAAGAACUCAGCACCCCCGCAUCGCAGGGCUCAGAAGGUCAUGAUCCGCUCCAGCAGUGACAGCAGCUACAUGUCUGGGUCCCCAGGGGGAAGUCCUGGGAGUGGCAGUGCUGAGAAGCCGUCCUCUGACGUGGACAUCAGCACACACAGCCCCAGCUUGCCUCUGGCACGGGAGCCAGUGGUGCUUUCUAUAGCAUCCUCCAGGCUGCCCCAGGAGAGCCCACCCCUCCCAGAGAGCCGGGACAGCCACCCGCCGCUGAGACUGAAGAAAUCCUUUGAGAUUUUGGUGAGAAAGCCUAUGUCCUCCAAGCCCAAGCCUCCACCCAGAAAAUACUUUAAAAGUGACAGUGACCCUCAGAAGAGUCUGGAAGAGAGAGAGAACUCCUCAUGCUCUUCUGGGCACACCCCACCCACCUGUGGCCAGGGGCUAAUUCUGAAGUCUCCCAUGAAGAGGAUGCAAUAUUGGAUGUGUUGAUGAAAAGACAAAACACAUUUGUGCUGUUCUAAGUUGUAAAGCUGCAUUGACUGCAGUUGGUAUCACAUGUGGCUGCCUGUAAAAGAGCUAACAAUUCAUGAAUGUCAACAGAUGUCAACUUACAGAGCUCCCAACCAGGAAGCGAGAGAGCUGCUGCCACUGCUGCUACCACAGGAAGACACAGCAGGGAGAAGCCCUAGUGCCUCUGCCGGCUGCCCAGGACCUGGUAUCGGCCCACAGACCAAGUCCUCCACAGAGGGCGAGCCAGGGUGGAGAAGAGCCAGCCCAGUGACCCAAACAUCCCCGAUAAAACACCCACUGCUUAAGAGGCAGGCUCGGAUGGACUAUAGCUUUGAUACCACAGCCGAAGACCCUUGGGUUAGGAUUUCUGACUGCAUCAAAAACUUAUUUAGCCCCAUCAUGAGUGAGAACCAUGGCCACAUGCCUCUACAGCCCAAUGCCAGCCUGAAUGAAGAAGAAGGGACACAGGGCCACCCAGAUGGGACCCCACCAAAGCUGGACACCGCCAAUGGCACUCCCAAAGUUUACAAGUCAGCAGACAGCAGCACUGUGAAGAAAGGUCCUCCUGUGGCUCCCAAGCCAGCCUGGUUUCGCCAAAGCUUGAAAGGUUUGAGGAAUCGUGCUUCAGACCCAAGAGGGCUCCCUGAUCCUGCCUUGUCCACCCAGCCAGCACCUGCUUCCAGGGAGCACCUAGGAUCACACAUCCGGGCCUCCUCCUCCUCCUCCUCCAUCAGGCAGAGAAUCAGCUCCUUUGAAACCUUUGGCUCCUCUCAACUGCCUGACAAAGGAGCCCAGAGACUGAGCCUCCAGCCCUCCUCUGGGGAGGCAGCAAAACCUCUUGGGAAGCAUGAGGAAGGACGGUUUUCUGGACUCUUGGGGCGAGGGGCUGCACCCACUCUUGUGCCCCAGCAGCCUGAGCAAGUACUGUCCUCGGGGUCCCCUGCAGCCUCCGAGGCCAGAGACCCAGGUGUGUCUGAGUCCCCUCCCCCAGGGCGGCAGCCCAAUCAGAAAACUCUCCCCCCUGGCCCGGACCCGCUCCUAAGGCUGCUGUCAACACAGGCUGAGGAAUCUCAAGGCCCAGUGCUCAAGAUGCCUAGCCAGCGAGCACGGAGCUUCCCCCUGACCAGGUCCCAGUCCUGUGAGACGAAGCUACUUGACGAAAAGACCAGCAAACUCUAUUCUAUCAGCAGCCAAGUGUCAUCGGCUGUCAUGAAAUCCUUGCUGUGCCUUCCAUCUUCUAUCUCCUGUGCCCAGACUCCCUGCAUCCCCAAGGAAGGGGCAUCUCCAACAUCAUCAUCCAACGAAGACUCAGCUGCAAAUGGUUCUGCUGAAACAUCUGCCUUGGACACAGGGUUCUCGCUCAACCUUUCAGAGCUGAGAGAAUAUACAGAGGGUCUCACGGAAGCCAAGGAAGACGAUGAUGGGGACCACAGUUCCCUUCAGUCUGGUCAGUCCGUUAUCUCCCUGCUGAGCUCAGAAGAAUUAAAAAAACUCAUCGAGGAGGUGAAGGUUCUGGAUGAAGCAACAUUAAAGCAAUUAGACGGCAUCCAUGUCACCAUCUUACACAAGGAGGAAGGUGCUGGUCUUGGGUUCAGCUUGGCAGGAGGAGCAGAUCUAGAAAACAAGGUGAUUACGGUUCACAGAGUGUUUCCAAAUGGGCUGGCCUCCCAGGAAGGGACUAUUCAGAAGGGCAAUGAGGUUCUUUCCAUCAACGGCAAGUCUCUCAAGGGGACCACGCACCAUGAUGCCUUGGCCAUCCUCCGCCAAGCUCGAGAGCCCAGGCAAGCUGUGAUUGUCACAAGGAAGCUGACUCCAGAGGCCAUGCCCGACCUCAACUCCUCCACUGACUCUGCAGCCUCAGCCUCUGCAGCCAGUGAUGUUUCUGUAGAAUCUACAGCAGAGGCCACAGUCUGCACGGUGACACUGGAGAAGAUGUCGGCAGGGCUGGGCUUCAGCCUGGAAGGAGGGAAGGGCUCCCUACACGGAGACAAGCCUCUCACCAUUAACAGGAUUUUCAAAGGAGCAGCCUCAGAACAAAGUGAGACAGUCCAGCCUGGAGAUGAAAUCUUACAGCUGGGUGGCACUGCCAUGCAGGGCCUCACACGGUUUGAAGCCUGGAACAUCAUCAAGGCACUGCCUGAUGGACCUGUCACGAUUGUCAUCAGGAGAAAAAGCCUCCAGUCCAAGGAAACCACAGCUGCUGGAGACUCCUAGGCAGGACAUGCUGAAGCCAAAGCCAAUAACACACAGCUAACACACAGCUCCCAUAACCGCUGAUUCUCAGGGUCUCUGCUGCCGCCCCACCCAGAUGGGGGAAAGCACAGGUGGGCUUCCCAGUGGCUGCUGCCCAGGCCCAGACCUUCUAGGACGCCACCCAGCAAAAGGUUGUUCCUAAAAUAAGGGCAGAGUCACACGGGGGCAGCUGAUACAAAUUGCAGACUGUGUAAAAAGAGAGCUUAAUGAUAAUAUUGUGGUGCCACAAAUAAAAUGGAUUUAUUAGAAUUUCAUAUGACAUUCAUGCCUGGCUUCGCAAAAUGUUUCAAGUACUGUAACUGUGUCAUGAUUCACCCCCAAACAGUGACAUUUAUUUUUCUCAUGAAUCUGCAAUGUGGGCAGAGAUUGGAAUGGGCAGCUCAUCUCUGUCCCACUUGGCAUCAGCUGGCGUCAUGCAAAGUCAUGCAAAGGCUGGGACCACGUGAGAUCAUUCACUCAUACAUCUGGCCGUUGAUGUUGGCUGGGAACUCACCUGGGGCUGCUGGCCUGAAUGCUUAUAGGUGGCCUCUCCUUGUGGCCUGGGCCUCCUCACAACAUGGUGUCUGGAUUCCCAGGAUGAGCAUCCCAGGAUCGCAAGAGCCAUGUAGAAGCUGCAUCUUGUUUAUACCUUUGCCUUGGAAGUUGCAUGGCAUCACCUCCACCAUACUCCAUCAGUUAGAGCUGACACAAACCUGCCUGGGUUUAAGGGGAGAGGAAAUAUUGCUGGGGUCAUUUAUGAAAAAUACAGUUUGUCACAUGAAACAUUUGCAAAAUUGUUUUUGGUUGGAUUGGAGAAGUAAUCCUAGGGAAGGGUGGUGGAGCCAGUAAACAGAGGAGUACAGGUGAAGCACCAAGCUCAAAGCGUGGACAGGUGUGCCGACAGAAGGAACCAGCGUGUAUAUGAGGGUAUCAAAUAAAAUUGCUACUACUUACCUACCACAUGCCAAGCACUGUGCUCAGGGCUAAACGGGCAUUGCCUUUAGUGAUCACAGCAGCUUCUACGGUGUAUGGUUCUGUGCCAAUGUAUUGAUAAGAGGGCACACACUGUGUACAGUAAAUGGCUUAUCCAGCUGGUGAGUGAUGCGGCAGAUUGAGUUUUCUUCUGUGAUUCGGUGGAGACUAUCAGCCCAAGAUGCUUUAAGUGCACAACAUUACAGGGAAUGCCUGAGUGCCUGGCCAAAGGGAUAUUUGGUUUGGCCAUCUCUGGAUGCCUGAUUGCCAAGCUCAGGACCAGGCAAUGUGACUUUGCAUCAGCAACAACCAGCAUCCCUUGACCAGGCCUGGGCCAGAGUAUUGGUCUCCUCUCAGCCCCUGAUCCUGUGAAGUAAGGAUGUGGGGGAAGACCUGGCAAGGACACAGAUGAAACACAAACAAUAGUAAUUCUCAGGCCAUCAUCAGUGGAGCCAUGUUAAUGUAAUCUGAUGGCUUCUCCAGGGUCCACAGGAAGUGAAGAAUCUGUUUCCCAGCAGUGGACUCAAAACCCAUCUGGGCUCCUAACCUUCCUGUAAACCCCUUUAGUGGCUUCAUUAGAGCAGGCGUUCAGCUCACUGUUCUAUUCAUCUCAAGGAAUAAUGGGCUUAGAGCAGUUUCUGUCCUGCUGGUUAACUUGUUUGGCCUAUUCCAUUCUGGAUUUUGUCAAGCAGUAGACAAGCAAUUAGACAAGAACUUGGAGGCACCAUUUGUAUCCACUUUUUAGACUUAAUAGAAACAUUGAAGAUGAACAUAAUCUACCAACGAAAGACGUGAUUCAAUUCAACACUCCCUUCCCAUGACCCAGGCUGGGCAAGGAGGCCACGUGAUGUGGAGGGCACAUUCCUUGCCUGCACAAACUCACCAUCUGUGCACGCAGUGGCCUUCCCUAAAAUCAGGGAAUUGUUUUAAGUCUUAUCAAGCAGCCAAGGGAUGAAAGAGAAGGUGGGUUUUCAUCAAGACUGGAAGGUGGGGACAGGGAUGAGCAUGGAGCUGGCCGUGGGCCUGGGGUACCAAGAGACUCCUUGAGAGACCAGGCAAAGCAAGUGAUUGGGACAGAGGUUAUCUGUCCCAGGUUAUCUGGGCAUAGAUGCAGGUGAGCCCAUGGCCCUCCCAGUACCUCCUGUCUCUGGCCUGUUUUAGAAGGUUCUCUCCUCCCCAAGGAGACACAACAACUCCUAGGGCCACUGAAGAUAUAACUAUUGCCCAGGUUUCUGGUCUCUAGGCUGGGGAAGUCCUCUGGGUAGGAAUCAGCAAGAAGAUCCUAAAACAAAAGCUCAUCCAUUUGCGUUCCAUGAUGCUGGGAUUUACACUUGAGGCUUAGCUUUGCUCUGCCAACUUCUUCAGAGCUGACACAGGAUGAAGGCAAUGCCAUCCUCAAACACUGCAGGCAUCACAGCUAACAAUUGUGAAGUCGUCUUAACUCACCAUAAAAAGGAAUCCACUCCCAGGCAGCCCUACUUCUUUGCUUUGCCCAGCAUUUUACUGAUUCAUACAUUAUCUCACUUGUGCCAACACUCAAGAAGCAGGCUACACUGACACUGGUAUUCCUGCCUCCAUAUUUUCUUUAAAAGACAAAUCAAAGCAGAUAUAUUAAGUGACUGUUCAAGAGCACACUUGGCCCAAGUGGCAGAGCUUGGACUGGAUGCAUGUUUUCCAGCUCCUCAUCCAGGGCUCUGACCAGUUUAACCUGAUGCAGUCACGUGGAGGAGCAGUGCAGGCACAGUAUGUCCCAUAGGCCCAGUGAGAUGCAUUCUUGGUUGGCUGGCCUUCCACUUGGCUACACAGGGAUGUACAAGGCGAUCCCAUCUUGAUAAGACCACCACCUCAGAGUAUGGAGCUCAGAGAGGGCAGGCAUGAAGUUUCCUUGGCUGGUGCACCUAGAAUUGGCUGAACUCAUGAGAAGUUGAUAUAGAACAGUGCUUGCCACAGAGCGGGGACUCGGUAAGCACUUAAUGAAUGAAUGAAUUCUAAGUCAAUCCAAGAGUCUGAUGAUUUCUUGAAAAGGGUGUUAGCUAAAGGAUCUUAGGCAUGACUGUAGAAUUUGUAGUUGCAAUAGAACAGAGAAAGAGGAAGCUUUCUGUCUCCUUAACACUGAGCUGUCAUGUUUUAAAGCUUGCUCACAUCUUGGCACAUUUAAGAGACAGUCACCCCAGGACUCAAAAAUAGGGAAGUAACAGUAACGCAGGGGAAACGUUUUCUGUUUGGAGGAGCAAAGGCUGAGAACACUGUGAAAACAUUUUGCGCGCACAAUAGUAACCUGGGUAAAUGCAGCGUGAAGGGAUUUUAGUCACACGUGGUCUUUCUUACAAGGAAGGUGGUGGGGGUGCAGAUGAGGUUGCUAGAGAAUGUUAGAGGAUCCCUCUCUGGAUUGGAGAUAGGGAAAGAAAGUUGCACGGCUGCUGAGGCCCCUUCUAGGUGGCAAGGCUGUGCUCCCUGGUUCUGAUGAUGUGCCUGGGUGGACAUGGCCCCUGUGAGUUUGUACAGUCUUGCAGCAGGAUCUAGAGGGGGGAUUUCCAGCCAGGGCUGCUAGACGGAGGCCUACUCUUCCAUCUUUCCUGAUGGCAGGAUGGCCUGGCCAGGGCCUGGAAGACAGAGACCUCCUGCCUCCGCCUCAGUAAGACGACAAGGAAAGGCAAAUGCCCAAGGGAAAGAAAAGGAAGGCUCUUCUCCCCAGAGUUCCCCAUGCAGACAUGAGUGCGUGCUCAGUUCAGAAUCACUUCUGAGAACUCAUCCCUAAUGCUGCAGAUUUGGGCUGGAACAGAUUCACACUGUCUGGUUUCACCGAGGACAUGAAACUCCACCUUGCGGGGAUAAAGAGAGAAAAACAAAUUCAUCAAAUGGAAGACACAUUGAAAGUGUUUUUCCUUAAUGCUUAUCCUGUUUUUAAACCAUUAUUUCCAAGUUGACACCUUUUUUAAGGAAAAAUAAAUAUUUUGCGGCAUUAAAGCCAUAUACAAGGUCUAUAUCAGAAAAAUAUAUUUGGGGGGCUGCAGCACAGGACUGAGGGAGCGGUACAUGCUUAAAAGGCAACAGGGCCUGGUUUUCAGUGGCGAUGAUGAUUCUCUAUGACAGUCAGGGAAACGUGGUCUCUGAGAGUGAUGGGCACAUAAAGCCUUGGUGCCAGAGUGCAUCGCAUGGUGUCCAGGCCGAGUCUCUGUCAGAUGGUUAGAGGCCUGGGUCUACCCUGCCAGGAGAGGCGUGUUUGGGUAACAGGCAGAUGGAGUUUGGAACACAUGAAUGGCUCAUCACACGCCAACCCUGAGUGGGGCAGGAGGCAGGAAGGGUGGGCUGCCGCCUCUGGUUGGCAUUCUCAGAGAUGCGCAGUCCAUCAGCUUGUUCCAAAGAGUGAACACAGGCCUCUGCGUGCUCCCAGGCUCCUUGGUGUCCCAACAGCUGGAGCUCCUCGAUGAGUCACGGGAGUUCUUUGCCAAGAAGUAACGAUAGCAUUACUCAUGGAAUUGCUUCACUGCUUUCUGAAGGUUGGCAUAAAACCGGGUCAUGCUGCGGGGGAAGAAGGAGUCCACCACGUUCUGUGGGAGGUAACCGCUGAGGUCGGUAUGGAAGAAUGUGACCAGGUUGGUCUUGGUGGGUUCCCUGUGAAGGCAACAGCAGAGCUGUGUUAUGAUCUGCAGCAGAGGUGCUGGGGACGAGCGCCAGGCAGGUGAGCAGAGCCCAGCCCAGUGGAAAUGGCCAUGAUACAGUGAUCGCGUCUCAUCCCUUGCUGUGCCCUCCACCCAGGAGUCCUCUCUGGACCUGCUGAUUUUCAGGAUGGAAACCCAUCCUGUCGGGGAUGCAUUCCACAGCCUCUCCCGGCCUCCAGGGAGGAAGAAGUCCCUACUCCCAGCCCAAAAACCCAGUACCCUGCUGCCCGAUUCACUCAGCAAAUGCUUUCAGAGAACUCACUUUGUGCCAGGCCCUGAGAGGAACGAAGAGAUGCUGCCCUUCACUAUUUAGGGUCUGCAACCUCCUGGGGGCUCCUGGGACCCUUUCAAGGGGUCUACAAAGUUAACACUAUUUUUAUAACAACACGAACAUGUGAUUCGCCUUCUCUCACAUGCAUACAGUGGGGUUUUCCGGAGGUUACAUGAUAUGUGAUAUUGCAACAGACUACACGCACAAGCAGGUAUGAGUUUCUGUUAAGCCUGGCAUGAAAGAGAUGGGCAAAAAUAUAAAAACAAUGCCACUCUUUUCACAGUAUUUUUUGUUUUAAAAAAAUAGUUUUUUAAAAUAAAAAUGUUAUCUAUGUUAA